AGCAACGCGCUGGCUUGUGUUAACAACCGGCCCGGGAUCAGAGGUCUGGGUCAACUGGGGGGCGGCAGCGGCGCUAAGCGGACUGUAUGGCGGUGGCCUAGGCCCCUGGCGGAAUUUUGGGACCUUUCGCGACUCUAGCGACUCUCAGGCUGCCUUCCCUUCUCGGUGGCGGGGCCUCUUUGGGCCCAGCGGCUGCGGGCGCACUGUAGGACAGGAAGAUCCCCCCACUCUCCACCCCGCCGCCACCGGCCAUGUGGACAGAGGAAGCCGGGGCGACCGCCGAGGCCCAGGAAUCCGGCAUCAGGAACAAGUCUAGCAGUUCCAGUCAAAUCCCGGUGGUUGGGGUGGUGACGGAGGACGAUGAGGCGCAGGAUGUUUUCAAGCCUAUGGACCUUAAUCGUGUCAUCAAACUCCUCGAAGAGACUGAUAAAGAUGGCUUGGAAGAAAAACAACUUAAAUUUGUCAAGAAACUGGUACAGUGUUAUCAGAAUGGACUUCCAUUAAGGGAUUUAGCACAGAUAUUUAAAAUUCUGAAUCUGUGUUCAGGAAAAAUAAAAAACCAGCCUCGUUUUAUAGAAUCUGCAUAUGAUAUCAUAAAACUGUGUGGCUUGCCAUUUUUGAAAAAGAAAGUGUCGGAUGAAAUAACUUAUGCUGAAGAUACUGCUAAUUCAAUUGCACUUCUGGGUGACUUAAUGAAAAUACCAAGUUCUGAAUUGAGGAUACAAAUUUGUAAGUGUAUUGUUGAUUUUUAUCAUGCAGAACCACCAAAGAAGCAUAUUCCAGGUUACCAGCAAGCGAGUUCAUCAUACAAGAUUCAAAUGGCUGAAGUUGGAGGAUUAGCAAAAACAAUGGUCCAGUCAAUGACCUUGCUUGAAAAUCAACUUGUUGAGAAACUUUGGGUACUUAAAGUUCUGCAGCAUCUCUCAACUUCUGAAGUUAAUUGUACUAUAAUGAUGAAAGCACAAGCAGCCAGUGGAAUCUGUACUCACCUCAAUGACCCAGAUCCCUCUGGACAGCUUUUAUUUCGUUCAUCAGAAAUACUUUGGAACUUGCUGGAAAAAUCUUCAAAAGAAGAAGUCAUACAACAGCUUAGUAACUUGGAAUGUUUGCUGGCUUUGAAGGAAGUAUUUAAAAAUCUGUUUAUGAGAGGUUUCAGUCAUUAUGACCGUCAGCUUAGAAAUGACAUAUUAGUGAUCACUACAAUUAUAGCUCAAAAUCCUGAAGCACCAAUGAUUGAAUGUGGCUUUACCAAGGAUUUGAUACUGUUUGCCACCUUUAAUGAAGUUAAAAGUCAAAAUCUUUUGGUAAAAGGACUUAAGCUUUCUAAUUCCUAUGAAGAUUUUGAGUUGAAGAAAUUACUAUUCAACGUAAUUGUGAUCUUAUGUAAAGAUUUACCUACUGUACAGCUAUUAAUUGAUGGCAAAGUUAUUUUGGCUUUGUUUACCUAUGUUAAGAAGCCUGAGAAGCAAAAAAUAAUUGACUGGUCUGCAGCACAGCAUGAAGAAUUACAACUGCAUGCAAUUGCCACUUUGUCAUCAGUGGCUCCUUUAUUAAUAGAAGAAUACAUGUCAUGCCAGGGAAAUGCUCGAGUCCUUGCAUUUCUAGAAUGGUGUGAGAGUGAAGAUCCGUUUUUCAGUCAUGGUAACAGUUUUCAUGGUACAGGUGGCCGAGGCAACAAGUUUGCCCAGAUGCGUUACAGUUUAAGACUCCUGAGAGCCGUGGUCUACCUUGAAGAUGAGACUGUAAACAAAGAUCUUUGUGAAAAGGGAACAAUUCAGCAAAUGAUAGGAAUCUUUAAAAAUAUAAUAAGCAAGCCUAAUGAAAAGGAAGAAGCCAUUGUUUUGGAAAUCCAGUCUGAUAUAUUACUUAUCCUAUCUGGCCUUUGUGAGAAUCACAUUCAAAGGAAGGAAAUUUUCGGAACUGAAGGAGUAGAUAUCGUUCUUCAUGUGAUGAAAACAGACCCCAGGAAGUUACAGAGUGGCUUAGGCUAUAAUGUACUUCUUUUUAGUACAUUGGACAGCAUUUGGUGCUGUAUUUUGGGAUGUUAUCCCUCAGAGGAUUAUUUUCUUGAAAAGGAAGGCAUUUUUCUCCUUUUGGAUUUGUUAGCAUUGAACCAAAAAAAAUUCUGUAAUCUAAUACUUGGAAUAAUGGUUGAAUUUUGUGAUAAUCCCAAAACUGCAGCUCAUGUCAAUGCUUGGCAAGGGAAGAAGGAUCAGACAGCUGCUAGUCUUUUAAUUAAAUUGUGGAGAAAGGAGGAAAAAGAACUAGGAGUAAAACGUGAUAAAAAUGGGAAGAUCAUUGAUACAAAAAAACCUCUAUUUACUAGCUUUCAAGAAGAGCAAAAAAUCAUCCCACUGCCUGCUAACUGCCCAUCUAUUGCGGUUAUGGAUGUUUCUGAGAAUAUUAGAGCAAAAAUUUAUGCUAUAUUGGGCAAACUAGAUUUUGAAAAUUUACCUGGCCUAUCUGCUGAAGAUUUUGUCACCCUUUGUAUCAUACAUAGAUAUCUUGAUUUUAAAAUUGGAGAAAUAUGGAAUGAAAUAUAUGAAGAAAUAAAAUUAGAAAAAUUAAGACCAGUCACUACAGAUAAAAAAGCUUUGGAAGCUAUUACAACAGCAUCAGAAAAUAUUGGAAAGAUGGUUGCUUCUCUGCAAAGUGAUAUAAUUGAAAGCCAAGCAUGCCAAGACAUGCAAAAUGAACAAAAAGUAUAUGCAAAAAUACAGGCCACGCACAAGCAAAGAGAGCUGGCUAAUAAAUCAUGGGAAGAUUUCUUGGCUAGAACAUCAAACGCUAAAACGUUAAAGAAAGCAAAAAGCCUUCAAGAAAAAGCUAUAGAAGCCUCCAGAUACCAUAAACGACCACAAAAUGCAAUAUUUCACCAAACACAUAUUAAAGGCCUUAACACAACGGUGCCCUCUGGUGGAGUAGUAACAGUGGAAAGCACUCCUGCCCGAUUAGUAGGAGGACCUCUGGUUGAUACGGAUAUUGCUCUUAAAAAACUGCCCAUUCGAGGAGGAGCCUUGCAGAGGGUGAAAGCAGUUAAAAUUGUGGAUGCACCAAAAAAGAGUAUUCCUACGGAACCCUAAGCAUGGGUAGGAGCAUACAACGAGAUGCCCAUACAAAAAAUACCAGAUACAUCUUAGGUACACUUGAAUUGAUGUGAAGUGUCCAUGGCUAACAAUGAAUCUUUGCUCCAUUUUGUAGACUAUAAGCUCUCUAAGAACAAGGUAGAGACCAUAUCUCAUUAAUUAUUGUACUUAGUAUCUCCGGAAAUAAAUUAUUAGAUAAUGUGAUGGUGGCCUCAGCUACUGGCAGUCUUUCCCUUGAGCUCUGCAAAUGCAGCAAAGUACUGAGCUCAAAGGGAAGAUUCAGCCAACAAAAUACUACACAAGUAAUGCUCAACACAGACAACAUGUUAGUUUAAAUGUAUUUACUUCAUAACAUGAUAGAUUUUCUCCAAAAUGGUGAGGCAUAAAUACUACUACAUGAAUAUAACCAAGGUGUGGAAAUAGUAUUACUUGCUUGAGUAUCAUUUUUGUAUGUAGUACAACUAAAUGUCUCAGAUUGAUUAGGACUGUAAUCUAGACAAUUUCUGAUGUCUGUGAACCUUUCUUCUUCCAUGUAUUUUGCCCAUCAGCAAGAAGAAAGGUAAAACAGGGCAGAUUAUUAUGUAGCAGCUAUUUAAUAGACAAAUAAGUGUAAGUUGAUGGAAAGCAGUAAUGUUCCUUAAUACAGACACUUGCACUUGGUAGACAGAUUCACCCAAGUUUGCAUAUUAUAAUUCCAGCCACCACACAGUGAGUGAGUGACUCUUUCUCACAAUAUCACUAACUCUAAGUCUCUGUCUCUCAUCACAUCCUAUAUUCUCACACCACCCCUGAGCCCUAGGGGACAUGAUGCCUACCCGAUCCUGCCGGCUGAGAGAAGGAUGGUAUAUUUUCUUACAUUAGUCAGGUGAGACAAAAUUUGAAGCUUUCAAACUGAAACUUUUACUAACCAACUGAAUGAAAAGGAAGUCAAAAGAAUAAAAGUGUGGAAUUCAGUGAGCACAGAUAAAAGUAGCUUCAACAAUCUCAGUAAUGAGACUUUUACCACAUGGGGGAGCUCAUUCUAGCAUGGUUAAACUAAUUGUCAGACAGUGCUGACUUACAUUGAGUGAAAAAUUAGUGAAUAAUUAGGUGAAUAACUUUCAUCCAUCUGGCAUCAUCAGUCUGCCUUAUGGAACAUAAAGUAUUUUAUAUACAACUAUAUUAUCCACCUUAAGUCUUUUGAGGUCAGAUAUCCAGUUUCUUUCAUCAUUCUUCUGAUAAUGUAGUUUCUAGAAUGUAUGAAUCUGGUCAGCUCCAUCUGAAGUGCUACAAUUUGUUAAUACUCCUCUAAACUGUGACCAAACAGAUCAAAGAUUUUUCAGGUGAGCAGGAUCAAUGUAGUUCCUCUCAUUUUUACACACAUUCUGCCAACACAACCUUAACUUACAUUAGUUUCAUUAGCAACCAUUUUUUAUUGCUUAUAUUUAGUUGCCUUUCAAGGAAAAUGUCAGGGAUGCUUUCUGAGAAAGAAUAGCAGACCCUGACAUCCAGGAACUGUCCUGGUACUAUCAGGUCAAAAUUCUAUAGAUAGACCCAAUACCCCAACUUUGGUUUCCAGUAUCAUUCUCCAAUAAAAUGAGCCAGGGCUUCUUGGAGAAAUGGCUAAUUCUAAGGCUGGCGCAGAAAUAUAUGAGUCUGGAGCAUCUUACUGAGCUCCCAGUGGCCAAAGCUGGAAUGAUUUGAACAAAUCAAUAAUGUAGUGUUGGAUUAUAAACCAAAGUAUAAACAAAUGUUCAUAAAUCCAUACUGAUAUAAAUAAAUGAUGAAAGGAAGGGAAAAAAGGAAGGAAGGGAGAGAGAAAGUGGGGGAAGCCUCCAUACAAAGAAUUCUAAAUGAUUUAUGUAGAUAUUCCCUCCUCAAGAAGGUAGAAGAUAACUACCCAUUCUCAAGUAUGGGUUAUGCUUAGUGACUUCUUUCCAGAGGAUGUAAUAUAGAAAGAAAGUGGAAAGAAACUUUACAAUGAAGAAAACUGGCAAACACUACCUAAGCCAAGGUUAAACACCACCAAUGGCAAGUCACGUCAAUGACAUGUGCCUUUGAUAUGACGUGUUGAGUAUGAUACUUUACCUCUGUGGUCUUCAUCCCAAAAACCUAUAAUCCCAGUCAAACAAAGACAUCAGGCAAACCCAAAUUGAGGGGCAUUUUGCAAUAUACCUGACCAGUACUCAAAAUUGUCAAGGUCAUCAAAAACAUGGUCUGAGACAUUGUCACAACCCACAGGAACCUCAGAAGACAUGACAACUCGGUGUAACGUGGGAUCCUGGAACAACAAUAACAAAAAAGGAGCUUAGGGAAAAACUACUGAAAUCUGAAUAAAAUAGGAAGUUUAGUUAAUAUUGUAUUGGUUUCAGUGUAUUAGUUGUGACAUAUAUAAUGUUAAGAUAUUAACAAUAAGAAUAAACAUGGGGCCAGGCACAGUGGUUCAGGCCUGUAAUCCCAGCACUUGGGAGGCUGACUCAGGCAGAUCACUUGGGUCCAGGAGUUGGAGACCAGCUUGGGCAAUGGAGUGCAAUCCUGACUCUACAAAAAAAUACAAAAAUUAUUUGGGAGUGGUGGUGUAGACCACAACCGUAGUUCCAGCUAUUUGGGAGGCUGAGAUAGGAGGAUCAAUUGAGCCCAGGAGGUUGAAGUUGCAGUGAGCCGUGAUUGCACCACUGACAGAGCAAGACCCUGCCAAAAAAAAAGAAAAAGAAAAAAAAAUGAUGAGAGGUAUAUAGGAACUCUGUACCAUCCUUGCAACUUCUCUGCAAAUUUAAAACUUUUUUUUUUUUUUUACAGUUUGGUAUUUUUUAUUAUUAUUAUACUUUAAGUUUUAGGGUACAUGUGCACAAUGUGCAGGUUAGUUACAUAUAUAUACAUGUGCCAUGCUGGUGCGCUGCACCCACUAACUCAUCAUCUAGCAUUAGGUAUAUCUCCCAAUGCUAUCGCUCCCCCCCCUGCUUUAAAACUAUUUUAAAAUGAAAAGUUUAUCAAAUUUACAAGAAGAAAAACAUUAAAAAGUGGGCAAAGGACAUGAACAGACACUUUUCAAAAGAUGUCAUACAUGGAGCCAACAAGCGUAUGAAAAAAAAGCUCAAUAUCACUGAUCAUUAGAGAAAUGCUAUGAAACCACAAUGAGAUACCAUCUCACACCAGUCAGAAUGACUGUUAUUAAAAAGUCAAAAAACAACAGAUGCUGGCGAGGUUGCAGAGAAAAGAGAAUGCUUAUACACUGUUGCUGGGAGUGUAAAUUAGUUCAACCAUUGUGGAAAGCAGUGUGGCAAUUCCUCAAAGAGCUAAAAACAGAACUACUAUUCGACCCAGCCAUCCCAUGACUGAGUAUAUGCUCAGGGGAAUAUAAAUCAUUCUACCGUAAAGACACACGCACAUGAAUGUUCACUGCAGCACUAUUUACAAUAGCAAAGACAUGGAAUCAACCUAAAUGACCAUCAUGACAGACUGGAUAAAGAAAAUGUGGUCCAUAUACACCAUGGAAUGCUAUGCAGCCAUAAAAAGAAUGAGAUCAUGUCUUUUGCAAGAACAUGGAUGGAGGUGGAGGCCAUUAUCCCUAGCAAACCAACACAGGAACAGAAAACCGAAUACCGCAUGUUCUCACUUAAGUGGGAGCUAGAUGAUGAGAACUCAUGGACACAAAAUGCGGAACAACAGGCACUGAGGCCUACUUGAUUGGUGGAGAGUGGGAAGAGGGAGAGGAUCAGGAAAAAUAACUAUUGAGUACUAGGCUUAGUACCGGGGUGACAAAAUAAUCUGUACAACAAACCCCCGUGAAAUGAGUUUACCUAUAGAACAAACCUGUAUGUGUACCCCUGAACCUAAAACAAAAGUUUAAAAAAUAAACAAAAUUAAAAGUUUAUUUAAAGUUUAAAAAAGAUUCUGGCCAGGCUUGGUGGCUUACGCCUGUAAUCCCAGCACUUUGGGAGGCAGAGGCAGGUGGAUCAUCUGAGGUCAGGAGUUUGAGACCAGACUGGUGAACCUGGUGAAACCCUGUCUCUACUAAAACUACAAAAAAUUAGCUGGGCAUGGUGGCAGGUGCCUAUAAUCCCACCUACUUGGGAGGCUGAGGCAGGAGAGUCACUUGAACCCGGGAGGCGGAGGCUGCAGUGAGCCAAGAUCACGCCAUUGCACUCCAGCCUGAGCAACAAGAGCGAAACUCCGUCUCAAAAAAAGAAAAAAUAAAGAUUCGAUAGAAACAGCAGAGGAACUUUAGACAUAGAUAAUUAUUAUCCCUUGUAUCAUCUUAUGAAGAAAUAUUUGUGGGGUCAAUAUUAGAUCCUUUGCCACCUUUUUUCUCCUCAGCCUUAAGCUCUCUGAAAAAUAAUCGGUUAUGAGCUAAGCCAAAUGAGCUCAGCAUAAACCCAAAGCUGUGAAACUGAAUCUUUACCAUGGUACCACUGCAAGAAUUGGUGGUUUGUUUUUUAAAAUGAUCUCUAGACUGUCAAAUGAUUUUGAAUAGGACAAAAGAGAAAUACAUAUUGUCCCAAUUCAGCUUCAUUUUGACCACCUUCUUUUUUAUCUUCUAUUUUGAUAUCAUAAAAUUGCUUUUGAAUUAGAUCUUUCAGUCUAUCCCUGCAUUGUCCCACUUCAGUGUCAACUCUGUGAGUCAAAGAUUACGUCUGGAUUGUUCACUAAUAUACCCUAAAGCUUAAUGAAUAUUUGUUGAAUGAAUGAAUGAUGAACAGAAAGAAAAAGUUUUUUUAUAUGCAGAUGACACUAUUUGUGCCAAAAACGGGGAGGAAUUUACGGUAUGUAAUCAUCAUCAAAAAGCUUAAGAUGAGUUGUUUUAAAACCAGAUUGCCCAGUUUAGCAAAUGUUCUUAUUUUUAACCCAAUGUAGUAUGUAAAUUCAAUUAAAAGAACUAGAAAACCAUUUUGCCAUUAACUGGAAGACUAAUUUUAUUGAUUUAAGCUAAAAUGUUUAUCAUCGCUGCAAUAAAAUUGUCAUGACAACUAUGA